AGUCGGCGCUGCGAAGUGGAGGCGCUGCGAGCGGAGCCGCGCGGAGGGCGCGACCGGCUGGUCCGGGCAGCGUGGGUUUGCCGCCUUCGGGGCUCCAGUCCGCGCGCCAGGGCUCGAGCAGUACCGCGGGCCCCUCAGGUGGGCCUCGGCUCGGGACGCCGGGAGUCGGGACCGCCAGUCGGGGCGCCGGGACCAUGGCGCUGCGCGCCCGGGCGCUGUACGACUUCAGGUCGGAGAACCCAGGAGAGAUCUCGCUGCGAGAGCACGAGGUGCUGAGCCUGUGCAGCGAGCAGGACAUCGAGGGCUGGCUCGAGGGGGUCAACAGCCGCGGCGACCGCGGCCUCUUCCCGGCCUCCUAUGUGCAGGUGAUCCGCGCCCCCGAGCCUGGCCCGGCGGGAGACGGCGGCCCGGGCGCCCCGGCCCGCUACGCCAAUGUGCCCCCCGGGGGCUUCGAGCCCCUGCCUGUCGCGCCCCCCGCCUCCUUCAAGCCGCCGCCUGACGCCUUCCAGGCGCUGCUGCAGCCACAGCAGGCGCCGCCUCCGAGCACCUUCCAGCCGCCCGGCGCGGGCUUCCCGUACGGCGGGGGCGCCCUGCAGCCGUCGCCUCAGCAGCUCUACGGCGGCUACCAGGCCAGCCAAGGCAGCGAUGAUGACUGGGACGACGAGUGGGACGACAGCUCCACGGUGGCGGACGAGCCGGGCGCUCUGGGCAGCGGAGCAUACCCGGACCUCGACGGCUCGUCUUCGGCGGGUGUGGGCGCAGCCGGCCGCUACCGCCUGUCCACGCGCUCCGACCUGUCCCUGGGUUCCCGCGGCGGCUCGGUCCCCCCGCAGCACCACCCGUCGGGGCCCAAGAGCUCGGCCACCGUGAGCCGCAACCUCAAUCGCUUCUCCACCUUCGUCAAGUCCGGCGGGGAGGCCUUCGUGCUGGGGGAGGCGUCAGGCUUCGUGAAGGACGGGGACAAGCUGUGCGUGGUGCUGGGGCCCUAUGGCCCCGAGUGGCAGGAGAACCCCUACCCGUUCCAGUGCACCAUCGACGACCCCACCAAGCAGACCAAGUUCAAGGGCAUGAAGAGCUACAUCUCCUACAAGCUGGUGCCCACGCACACGCAGGUGCCGGUGCAUCGGCGCUACAAGCACUUCGACUGGCUGUACGCGCGCCUGGCGGAGAAGUUCCCGGUCAUCUCCGUGCCCCACCUGCCCGAGAAGCAGGCCACCGGCCGCUUCGAGGAGGACUUCAUCUCUAAGCGCAGGAAGGGCCUGAUCUGGUGGAUGAACCACAUGGCCAGCCACCCAGUGCUGGCGCAGUGCGACGUCUUCCAGCACUUCCUGACGUGCCCCAGCAGCACCGACGAGAAAGCCUGGAAGCAGGGCAAGAGGAAGGCCGAGAAGGACGAGAUGGUGGGCGCCAACUUCUUCCUGACCCUUAGCACGCCCCCCGCCGCUGCCCUUGACCUGCAGGAGGUGGAGAGCAAGAUCGACGGCUUCAAGUGCUUCACCAAGAAGAUGGACGACAGCGCGCUGCAGCUCAACCACACGGCCAACGAGUUCGCGCGCAAGCAGGUGACCGGCUUCAAAAAGGAGUAUCAGAAGGUGGGCCAGUCCUUCCGCGGCCUCAGCCAGGCCUUUGAGCUGGACCAGCAGGCCUUCUCGGUGGGCCUGAACCAGGCUAUCGCCUUCACCGGAGAUGCCUAUGACGCCAUUGGCGAGCUCUUCGCGGAGCAGCCCAGGCAGGACCUGGAUCCCGUCAUGGACCUAUUAGCGCUGUAUCAGGGGCAUCUGGCUAACUUCCCGGACAUCAUCCACGUUCAGAAAGGUAAAGCCUGGCCCUUAGAGCAGGUGAUAUGGAGUGUAUUGUGCAGGCUGAAAGGGGCGACUUUGACAGCAGUACCACUGUGGGUUUCAGAAUCAUAUUCUACAGGUGAGGAAGCGAGCAGAGACGUGGACGCCUGGGUCUUUUCCCUAGAGUGAGCUCUUACCAAAGUCAAGGAGAGUAGGCGACACGUGGAGGAAGGGAAGAUGGAGGUGCAGAAGGCUGACGGCAUUCAGGAUCGCUGUAACACUAUUUCUUUUGCCACUUUGGCUGAAAUUCACCACUUCCAUCAAAUUCGAGUGAGAGACUUUAAAUCACAGAUGCAGCAUUUCUUACAACAACAAAUAAUAUUUUUCCAAAAAGUUACCCAGAAGUUGGAAGAAGCUCUUCACAAAUAUGAUAGUGUUUAAUGACUGGACGUUGGAUUAUGGACUUUUUCAGUUCAAGGAUAAUUUCUACAGCAGAAUAAAAACUGCUGUCAAAGAGCUAUUGCCAGCUAUCAGUGGUGGUACAAGGACGGUUUUGUGUUCAUCUGAAACCCAGCUGAAUUUAUAAUUAUGUAGGAAAUAAACAGUUAAUAUGGUUAUAUAAUAGAAACAGUACCACACAUUGUAACUAAAUUAUACUAUGUAUGCCUACACUACCAUUGUAACUUUUGGAAUAAUGAUUAUACUAUUUGCCUUAUUGCUUUUUGAAGUAUGGGUAUUUUAGUGCAUACUUUGUAGACCUCAAAACCCAUGAAGGGUCUCAAAGAAGCUGGCUGGAUACAAGCCUGCUGUGGAUGCCUUUUUACUCUCAUAGAUUGGGAUUACCUAAAUUCAACCUAUUCUCUGUUUACAAACUCCAACUAGAGCAGCUAUGCGACCUUGUGCCUUUAGACUCUUGGUUUUUCAUUUCUCCCCGUCCCUUCCCCACCUUUUUAAAGUAAGCCACAGCUUUUCUGAUUGAAAGAGUGAAAGGCCAGUGCAUAUAAUGACAAACUGAUGAUAACCUUAUAUUGGCAGUAGGGGGUGGGGGGGGCGGUGGGGUGGGACGAUCAGCUGUCAUCAAUUUGCACAGCAAGUAUUAUCUCCUGAUAAGAUGCUGGUGAAUGCAGGGGAGUGAGAUUCAUUGCUCAUCUUUGGAUAUGAAGUCUGUUAGGGAAGAAACAGUGCCACUAUUCCCUUAGAUGCAACAGUAGCAUAGCCUCUUCACCCAGGCGUCCCAAAAGCUUGGCGUGAAGAUUUCAGCAAACAUGUCUUACAACAUGAGGAGGAGGAGUCUAAAUCAGUCAGGGGAUAAAAGUAUCGAAUCAUUGACAACACACACUUGGCUUUAGUUCUUAGGAGGGUUUUGUUUUUGUUUUUGUUUUUAGGUUGAAGAUUUUCUUUUAAUAUUCAGUUUUUUGAAAAAAAAUGGAUCUACACUGUUAACUGAUUGAGACUCCACUGUGAUUCACUUGUUUACUUAAAAACUUUUCAGGGAUGUCUGUAAAUUUCAGUGUUAAUAUGUCAUGAAAAGUGGUGUGGAUUGAUCUAAGGAGGGACCAGAAAUAAUUUUUGCUAUUCCAAAUACUGAAGGAAAAAGAUAAUUGAUUUAUACUAUGUUUUAAAAAAAAAAAAGGUAUUGAUGAGCCCCCCCCCCCCAGGACAUUUAACCUUAAAAUUUAUUUUAAAUGUAUUCUUUUAUUAUUAUAAGGGAAAUACAGAUGGCUGAUAAAUACCAAAAAGAUUCAAAAGCAGCUUAAUUUAAAAAGCACAAAGAGAUUCUGGCUUACAGUGCCCCAAUCUCAAUGUUUUUAUAGUUGCUGAGCUAACUAAUGUGAUUAUUGAGUUUACAGAUUUAAAAAUUGUCACUGUUAGAGUAUCUACUGUUUUUAUGAAGUCAAACUUAUGCUGCCUCAGAAAUCCCUGGGUACUGAAAUGGUAACAUGGAAGUGAAGAGGUCACUUUGAAAUAUUGGUGAGUCACAAAGAUUAAAGAAAAGGAUCAGUUUGCAGAUACUCAGAAAAGGUUAUUGAAAUAAUUACUGAACAGCACAUUUUCUCUCUAAAAAGUAGUUUCAUAUGGGUUGUAUUUUUAAGAUCAGAUUAUCAUUUUGAUAUUUGGUCAAAAUUUUGUACCUUAGGUUACUUAGAGCCAGAUUUAACAUCAUGAACAUUAUGUGGCUUUGUCUUUACUACAGAUAUGUGGAACUGUAACCAAAUAUGUUGUCUCUAAAACUUGUUGAUUGCAAAAUACAGUUCUAUAAACAAAACCCAUAUGUAUAUAUAAAUGUUAAUUUUGCGGAAGUCUGGAAAUUAUAACUAUAGCAUUUAAGUUUGAGUCUGUAUUGGACAAAUAAGCACCAUGCUUUUCAAAUGAUUUAAAAAUUACUUUUAUUUGCCUCUUUAUUUUGAUGGUGGUUGGAUUUUUUUUUUUUUAAUAGUAAAAUCACUAAACUUGUGCAAUGGUAGCAUGGAAAUUAUCUGAGGUAUAUUGUAUGAUUGUACUUUAGCCAGGGUGGACAUAGCUUAAAUUAUAAAAACUAAAGAUGAAAGUACAAGGAAGUAUAAGUUAUACUUAUGUAAGUAUAAAUUCAUGCUGCCUACUUCUAAGAGAAAUUUCAUUCUUCAUAACCACAUAACAUUAUAAUGCCACUGAUUCAUACGGGAUUUACAUUAAUUCUAUGGGGGAGGACACUAGAAUUAUUAGUGUUCAUUUUCAUCUAAGAUCUUUAUUCUCUAACGUUCUUGGUCCUAUUGAAACAUUGCAGUAUGCAAAACUACUGCAAUGUUAAACCCAAGAGAAAAGCCAUUAUCAUGUGUAUGCUGGUCAUCAUGAUCAGUGUGGUACAAUUUUUAAAAAUAAACUAUCAUGCCCUUCAUGCCAUUAUUUGUCUUUAUUUCUAUGAUUUAUAAUCCUGAUAUGUGAUGUGUUUGUAACACAGGGUGUGCACUUGAGCCUGGUUUUACUGUUUUUAUUAGACAGAGUUGUUUAUAUGCUGUAACUGUAACGCAGCGAGACUGGUUCUACAGCCAUGUGUCGUAAUCUUGUUCCCCGUCCAAGCUGUUGUAUCUGAAGGUACCCAGUUUGCACCCAGGAUGAGGGAACGCAUUCAAAAGUGAAAUGUAAAGCCAGUGCACGAAUAUUAUAGUAAUUGAGAUUUUCCCAGGCUUCACUGAUACAGUUGUUUUGCAUUUAUUCACAAUAAUACAGCAGAUUCUUAAAUGCCGAUUUUUAAUUGUCUUAAAUUUUGCUGCUGUUCUCAUAAUUAAGGACUUGAAAAAUGUUUUAGUCUGUCAAGUAUGUAAAGUUUGUGUAAAAACUUUUAAAUGUCAUUCUUAAGUUCAUUGCCAUAGCCAUUUUCCAUUUAUGUCUUCAUUUUCCAAAAAUCAAAUGCCAUGUCUGAUACCUUUAAGUCCAUAAGCAUUCAAUUUUCUCAUUUCCACCUUCAUCUUUGGUUAACAGAAUAAGUAAAACAGGGUAUUAUUUAUUUGUAGUCUAGAAAUGUUGAAUAUUGUUUUAUUUCCUUCAAAAUGUUAUGAUUAGUGCAGAUCAGCCAUGUUUAUCUUUUUAAAAAAUAAACAGGUUGCUUUAUUUCUUA